GUCGCCAGGACGCAGGCUCGCGUCAGGGCUGGCGGUAGGGCCCGCAGCUGUCGGCCUGGCGUCUUCACCCCGCGCAGUCGGCCUCGCCUAGCCUUCUCGCGCCUGACUGGCCGGACCCUGCCCCUGGCGGAGGUAACUGCCCGCGGAUUCCUUACCCCGCGAUCCUGGCCUCCUCGUAAGCUCCCCGGACCCGGGCGUCCUCGGUCUCCCCUCAUCUACUCUUCUGUCGGGCAGGUCCGCGACCUUCCGCCUCCCGGGCCGUCUCCCGCCGCACCCGGCCCUGGUACAUCCCCACUACCCAGUCCGGGCCCGUCCUCGCUCUGGGCCUACCCCAGCCUCCCAGCGUCGCCUGCUGACGGAGCGCGGGAGCCCCAAGGGGCCGGGGUCACCCGGCCGGCGUGGGUGGUGCCAGGCUCGGGCCACACCUCGGCACCGGACCCGAGUCCCCCAGCUUCUCGAGCAGGAUCCGGAGGAAUAGAACGUCAAUUUUCCUCGCUCUUAGCAAUUUUAAGAUUGACUAAUGGAUUUAGGAAUCUUGGGACUGUUUUACUUAAUUGGUCAUUGAUAGCUUAACAAACAUGGAGAUAAGAUUAGAAAUCUUGACAUCAACAGGUAUUAAGCAGAAAAAACCAUGGCCACGUGUCUCCUGGUUGGGAAAGGAAAAAGAAGCCGUUUUUCUUUUGGAUGAUAAAUUCAUAAAUGAAAUUAAUUUGCUAUCAGGAAAGAUAAAGAAGAAAAUUCCUAGUCUGCAGCCUUUCUUGAAGGAUGUUAUUGUCCUAACAACAUCCAGUAAUGAUGCCUGGCUGGCUGGGGUACUAACUACAGGAGAGCUUUUCCUUUGGAACAAAGAUCAAGAUUGUUUGAAAACUAUACCAAUAACUGAAAAGCCUAAGGAAAUGAUCAAAGCUACAGUCGCAAGCUCUUUGAGACUGUACUUGUAUGUAUCUGGAAAUGGGAAAAGAAUUGUGCUCAUAACACCUUCUGGAUGCAUAUUUCUUUGGGAAUAUUUGGAAUUAAAGAAUAUCUUAUCUUCUAAAAGCCUUUCAUUGGCGGGUCGGUGGUCCCAGGUCAUACCUGAAGAAGCAGUUCUCUUGCCUUCCACCGAAGAUAAAGAAGCUGUAGUGAAUGCUGUUUUUAUAAAAAAUGAGUUAUUUGGAGACUGCUGCCUGUGUUCAUUUACUUUUUAUUCUGGGGAAUGCCUGAAGUUAACAUUUCUAGCAAUUCGGUGGCAUGAGAAUGUAUUUACAUCUGUAAGAUCAUUGCCAUACCAUGUUCAUUGGGCUCAACAAGACUGUCAUCUCUGUAGUUUAAUUCCUAAAUGUGAAUCAGUAAAGUCAAGAGGAGCUCUAAUUUCUGCCUUUUCAAGAGAUGGCCUUACCCUGGCAGUAACUCUUAAUCAGAAAGACCCCAAGGCAACUCAGGUAUUAUUUAUAAACACACUGAAUUUUGUUACUCUCUGUGGUAGCCUUAAAGGAUGUAGUAACAAGAGUCCCGUGGUUCCAGCUACACUUAUUAGGUCCUACUGGGUAGGUGAUAUCAGCUGGACGCAUGAUAGUCUUUUUCUGGCUUGUAUGUUAAAACGUGGCUCUCUGGUUUUAUUGACCUGCCAAGGUGAAUUGCUAACAUUAAUUACAUUUGGUUGCUCUAUAGAAUUUGGCCCAGCAGAAUUUAUUCCUCUUCAUCCACUAAUAACGUAUAGACCACAGCAGUUUACGUUUCAAGAUUCAAAUAAUUCUGUUGAUUCAUCAGCUUCUGAUAGUGACCCUAUGAGACAGAGAUUUUCUAUAAAAGCACACUCACGGUUACCCUACCUCGUUAUAUCUGAUGGAUAUAUGGUCACAACCCUUCGAUUUCUUGAUAGCCUAUCUCCAUCAGUACACAUGAGAUCACUUCUACUUGAUUCAACCCAGAGGCUUGAGAAAAUAUAUCAAAGUGUGAUAUUGUCUAAGCCAAAAGGCAAAGGACUGAACUUGCGAUCACUGAAUUCCCUAAGGUCUAGCCUGUUAGAACACCAAGGAAAUGAAAGUUCAGCCGAUUUCACUGUCCCCAAAUUCUUGCAGGCAGAAGAAACAAUAAAUGAAAAUGCAGCAGAUUUUCAGGAUUUUGAAGCAGAAGAAACUAACGAAGGCAGACACUUUCCAGACAACUUAUGUCCUUUUUGGAACAAAAGAGAUGAUGUGCUGUGUAGUAGUAUGAAGGAAGGAAGAUUGGAAUUUGCAUCUAUGUUUGAUACGAUACAUGCAAAGGAUGAUAGUGAGGAGACAGAUAGAACCAUUACAGAACUGCAUUCUAUCCAGAAAAGUCUACUUGCAGCGUGGACUAUAGGAAUUUCAAAAACUGUGACAGAAAAAAAUUUAAUGUUAAAUUACAUAGUAGUUUGUAUCACUCAUUUUUUUUACAUUCUUCAAUUUAUAAAAUGUCCUUUUCCUAAACUUGAUCUUGUUUUAAGCAAAAGCUCAAGACAUAAUGCAUGGAUACUUUGUAUCUUUCAACUUUUUCAUCAGUGUUUAUCAAUCCAUUAUUGGGAUAUAAGAUACAAACAAGAUGUGGGGCAUUUGAUAAAGCUGACCUCAAAUACUGUAAAACUUUUGCUGACUCAGCAACAAAAGGGUCAGUUAUUCUCAGAGAAACUUUUAGCUUGUUUUUAUUUACUCAAAAUGGUAGCUGACAAUUUAAAUGGUGUAUACAUUCUUCAACCUGAAGUUAUUUCAGCAUCAGCUGAUGGAAGUAAAAUAACAGCUCAAGACUCAUUGGUGGUACCUAUUUUUCAGAUGUUUCAAGAUAGUGGUUUUCAGAAAAACUGGUCUUGGAACUCAUUUUUCAAGAUUCAUCCUCAAGUAGUAAAUCCUGUGCAACAGCCAGGACACAGAUUGCUUAUUCUCUGGAGAAUACUGUACAAAAAAACUUUAUGGUAUCAAGCACAAUUAAAUCGAAGAGUUCCUGAAGCUGAUAGUCAGUUAACUGAAAAGAUGACACAUGAAGCAUCUACUGUCAAGUCCCUGUUAUGUCAUUUGCAGGCUAACCUACAGAGUACUGGAGAUUGCUUGAAUCAAACCUUAGAACUUAAAUCUAUCAAUGGGGAAGAAUGUUUUUUAUUAGGAUCAUAUGAAAAGUCUGUUCAGCUGUGGAAAAAAGCUCUACAAGAAAUCGAAGAGAAAGGAGGAAGAAGGACGUAUUUUCUUCAGAUACGCUAUUAUCUUUCUCUCUUAUACUGCCACCUCUAUAGCUAUAAUUUAAAUGAUGCUCAAGGAUUGUGUGAUCAGCUAGCAAGAGAAAUCCUGAGAUGGUCCCAACUACCUGUAAAAGAAAAUAAAGAUUUUUCAGGUGCUGCAAAGUCUCAUUUUGAGUGUGGAAUGGUGGGCGGUGUUCAUCCUGAGGCAGCAGUGAGAGUCGUCCAGUCCAUGGCUCGUUUCAUGGCUGCCUAUUUCACCAAUCAGCAGCUUUGCAUUUUGCCCCCUCAUCAUGUGAAUGUUCUUCCCCCACUUCAUAUUAAAACAGAGCAGUCCUUUCGACUUAUUCCUCUGCAACACUCUAAGGUGGCCAGUGUUGUUAGAGAUCAGAAUCUCUCUAAUGUGUGGACAGUUGAAUAUGCACUUGAAUUACUAUUUAUUGGUGGCCUGGUUCCAGAGGCUGUGUGGUUGGCAUAUAAACUUGGAGACUGGAAGACGUCUGUUUCAAUUGGUGUGGCUUUCCAGCUGUUCUGUAAACGUGAUAGCAAUUUCAUGAGGUCCAAGAAAAAGAGUCUGAAUCUACCACUCCGUAUGACUCCAGCACAGAUUUUUCAGGAAAAACUGCAGUGUGUUUUAGGUCAACCAGCCUCUUUGGAAGCAAAAAAUGAAAUGGGCUCAAAAUAUAAACAGUUUACAGAUCCCAUUGAAGAGGAAGAUGCAAAUCUGCUAUUUGGUUCAGUACAAGAAGUACUGAAAGCAUCAGUUAUGGCCGAUGCAGAUAUUCUUUCGGAGACAUUUCAACUUCUGAUAGACUCUGCCAAGGACUUCAGUAAAAGACUGUGGGGCUUAGUGCCAUUCGGCUUGUAUCUUCCAGCUCCUCCAUUGUACUGUCCCCAGCCAGCUAUUCUUAGUGAAGAAGAUGGUGAUGAUCUUCUUUUAAAAGCUGAAAAAAAUAAUCGCCAGAAGGUAUCUGGAAUCCUUCAGCGUGUUCUCCUGCUUUUCCGGGCGGCUCAGUGUUCUUUUCCUGUAGCACAGUGGUAUAUAUUGCAGUUGAGGUGGGCAAGAAAAGUCAUGCAGAAGAUUCGAAUGAAAGGAUCCCUUCCUUCACUGAGUCCUUUUCCUCAGUCAUUACUUAAUUACUGUAAAGGAGGUAUCGCAUUUUUUAGACCUGGAGCAGCUGGAGACCACAAGCUUGAUGAAGUUUCCAUUAGAGCAAUAGGUUGCUUCAGAGAACUUUGUGCUCUGUGUUGGAUGCUGCAUGUCCGUGAUAAGUUAUCCUAUAGUUGCAGGCAAUAUCAGAAAGCAAGAGAAAAUGUAAAAGGAGAAAAGGACCUUGAAGUGGAGUUUGAUUCUUGUAUGAUUGAGCACUGUCUUAGUGCAGUGGAAUGGGCUUAUAGAAUGCUGCCUUUCUCUCGGUUUUUUAAUAUGGAAGAACUUAUUCAGGAUAUAAUUUUGAGCCUUAUUGGAGAACUGCCACCAAUCAGAAAGGUAGCAGAAAUUUUCGUGAAAGCAUUUCCCUAUCCUGAGGACGUGAGGGUUCCUUUAAGAGACAAAUAUCACUCUCUUCACCAGAGACUCAGACACUGUGUUGUGAAAGGACCCCAGACUGAGGAAAUGAUGUCUGUUGUCAUGCAUUCUAUCCAGAAAGUGAGGGUGAAAGCUCUAAAACGUGUGCAGAGAAAUAUAGGCUCUUUUGAAGUGAAUAUAUGGGAACCAAUUGAAGAAGAGAAACCAGAUGAGGCUCCAGGUGUUGACAGAUAUUCCCUGGGGACUAGUUUGAGCAGAAGUACACUCACAGAACUAGGAGAUUCUGUGGUUCACAGUGAUGCAGAUACGUUCUCUGAAGCUUUGUCGGUUGAAGAAAAAAGUAGGAUAAAUAUCUAUCAAAGAAAUGCCCCAAAUCACAUGGAAUUAACAUCAAUUCAUAAGCCAACUGAUAAAAGGAAAAUGUGUAAUCAGAAAGAAAAUCCUACAAAGAAAGAAGAUCAUGAAAAGUUAUCACAAAAUACACUUCCUGUAAUAGGUGUUUGGGAAUUUGAACGUGAUGAUGAUGAAUAUAUUAAAUUCCUUGAUCUGUUUUUGAGUUACAUUCUUGAAAGAGACCUACCUUAUUCCAGGGAUGCUGACAUUCCAUUUCUAACUAGUUUUUCUGGAAAGCUUAGAGAACAUGAACUUAAUUCUUUACUUUUUGAUGUACAUACAACAUUAAAACGACAUCAGAGCAAAACUAAAAGCCAGAAUGUGUUUAGAGCUGGUUCUUGCUUUGUUGUUGCUCCUGAGUCCUAUGAAUCAGAAAAAUCAUCCUCUUUAAAUGAUGAAUAUGGCAUGCAUUUAGAAAACCAGAAACUUUCAUCAUCAGUACUGGUUAAUCAAGGGAUCAAACCUUUUUUACAAUAUCCUUCGAAUGAAGUCAAUAAGAAUGAAGGAAUGAGUGGAUUAUUUGGUUUAAAACAAAGGUCAAUUUACAAAAUACAAGAUGACACUAGAGAGAAAUGUCUAAUCCAGAGAUCAUCAAACCACAUUUUUUGGACUCCCAAGUCCAUUAAAACUAGAAGAUGUAUUUUCAAAGCUAUUCAGUGCAAUGAUAUUAACCCUCAAGAAGAUCUUCCUUUAGCACUAAACACUUUUGGCAGUAUAGGAAGACUGCUGGAAUGGAUGAUAAGGUGGUCUAAUAGAAGGCUACUCUGUGAUUCUGGUAUAACUGAGUCAUCCUCUGAGUACAGUCCAGUAAUUCGUGUAAAGACCUCUACAGCUGCCAUUCUUACAUCAUUAUGGCUUUUGGAACAACCCUAUUUUGCUACAUAUAAGGCAAAAAAUGCCAUUAUUAAGAUGGUAGAGAAUCGUGACACUGGGUGUCAGAUUGGACCCAAUAUUGAGAGGGAGAGCAAAUCAGAUGCUGGCGGUUCAGUUGCAGUAGCAACUCCAGGUGGAACUGAGGAAAGAAAUGGUCAGAAUAAAUCUUGUCAAAAUAUCUUGAAUAGAAUGCCAACUGAAGCAAAAAAUCCUGAUAUAAAAGAAAUCAAUGAUGAUAUUAUUUCCAUCACUCAUAAUACUAAAAAAGAAUUUAUAGAUAUUGAUGAGAAUCUUUUAGAAGUAGAAGCAUUUACAGAAGAGGAAAUGGAUAUGCACAUAUCAGACUAUGAAGAAGACAUUGAAGAAUCUGUUGGAGGUUUCAGAAGUCCCAGUCUUGCCAUUUGCAUGAUGACUUUACCACAGCAGUUAGAAGAAGAGUUCACAGAAGAGGUUCAGUGUCAAAGGGAAGAACCACUGGAGACAAUUAUGGAGGAAAAAUCGACUGAACAAAAAGGUAUGAUCGAAGCCUUUUCACAUCCUGGGCAUACCACUCCUCAAUCAAUGCAAGUAGAUACGAGUUCAGAAAUUUCUAGUGCACAGAUUUCUACAUAUAAAGAAAAAUCUUCCUCAGUUCCACUUCUGAUAUCAAAUGGAGUCAAUGUUGCUUCACAACCACCUGCUCCAACACCUCAGAAGACCCAGAGAAAUGAAUUCACGGCUCAGUUACCAGAUUGUUCGGAGUCCGUUAGGCAGAUGCUGCAAGAUGAAAUGUUUAAAUUAGUUCAGCUGCAACAGAUCAACUUCAUGAGCCUAAUGCAAAUAGUAGGAUCAUCCUUUGCUAAUCUCCCAGAUACACAACAACUUGUACAGCAGUCUCAGUCUGUGCAUUUAGGGGAAAGCCAAGAAUCAAACCUAAGAGGAUGUGGUGAUGUUGAAGACAGCAACAAAAAUCUUAAGGAGAGAUUUUUUAUUAAACCACAGUCAAUGGGAGAGAACGCCAGAGAGCCUCGCAAGAACAGCCCACACUGCCAUGAAGGAACUAUCCCAUCUGGUCAAAAUAGUACUGGAAACGUACAGAAUGUUCCACAUGGGAGUAUUCCUUUAUGUCAAUUAAAUGGCCAGCCCCGGAAAAAAGGACCAAUUCCAUCAUCUCAAAACUUACCAUCCACUUCGUUUUAUCCAGCUCCUGCUGGAAAUACUCACCUCUACCUUUUGUCCACACCUUCUGUUGUUCAGAAGGCACCUAGACUUAUCCCACAUGCAAAAACAUUUAGUCCUGGUGAUGGCUUUCCUUUGCUUCAAUUUAAGUCUAAACAAGAAUUCCAGCCCCUUUUCUUACAUACAGGAAGUAUUCCACAAGUUCCCUUCAGGCCUUUGCCACAACCAAGAGAGGCUUGGGGAUUAUCUGACUCCUUCCAACCUGCUCUGCCACAGAGAGCAGCACAAACUACUCCAGCAUCCCAUUUGAAUGUAAGCCAGUAUAACACUGAAGCCAGAAAAAAAGAAGUUGAGCAGAAGACGUGGGCAGAAACUGUAAUUACAGAAAUUCCUAAUCAUGUGAACUUGGAUCAAUAUGUUGGACAAGAAAAUUUGACACCUCAACAGGACUCUUCAGUGUUUAUAAAACCAGAAAAACUAUUUGAUGUUAAGCCAGGGACCCUUGAGAUAUCUCCUCACCAUUCCUUUGGACUUCCGUUACUAUACCUGCCACUUAAACCUCCUAAUAUGUUUCCAUCAACCUCAAGAGCAUCUAUUACAGUUCCCUCAACACCUAUCCAACCUAUAGCAGAAGAAAGAAAAUACCCAAGAUUGUCAUUACUUCAUUCACAUUUGUCCCCAGAAAAUAGGUGCAAAAAAACACAACUUAUCCCACUUGAAAACCUCAUUGCGUUUAAACAAAGCCAACAGAAACUAACACAUAAUUUAUUUGAACAAGGUGAUGCUGGACACCUUCAACUUCUAAAGGUCAAAAUAGAACCACCUGAAGUAAGACAAGGAAAGGACAGUAAAAAAAGGCAAAGAAGAAGAGCUGAGAAAGAGCUGCAAGAAAAAAGAUGUGAGAAACUGAGGAGAAAACCAAAUGUGACUUUUCGACCAGAGAAUUCCAUAAUUAAUAAUGAUGAUUCAGAAAUCAUUAAGAAACCCAAGGAACAACAAGAACAUUGUGGUUCCCAUCCUUUGGAUGACUUCGACGUUCCUUUUGAAAUGCUACAAGAUGAUAAUACUUCAGCUGGAUUGCAUUUCAUGGCCUCUGUAAAAAAGAAAGCUAUAGGAAGUCAAGAUGCAAGUACAAAUACAGACCCAGAACAUGAGCCUUUGACUGCUCCUCAGCUCUUGGUCCCAGAUGUCUAUCUAAAUCUGAAGCUUUCCAGUGAAAUGUCAGAGAAACCUUGGUCACCCUCAAUACCUCAUACAGUAACAAACUUGGUUGGACAUACUUAUAUAAAUGUGAUUGACAUUGAAGCUAAUGAUCUUCUACAGGAAUUACCUGUGAGAGAAGAGCCUUCAAAUGAUAAUGUUAUCAAACAGCAAAGCGAUCAUCUAGCAGUUCCAUCGUCUGCAGAGUUACAUUAUAUGGCAGCUUCAGUUACUAAUGCUGUUCCCCCACAUAAUUUUAAGAGUCAAGAAGUAACUCCAGCUUGUCUGGAUGGAAAAAGCUUGAGAGCAGGCAUUACAGAAGUGAAGGAGCCUAGUGUCACCUCACCUACACCAUCAGACAUACAGCAGAACAAAGGUCUGCCAAAACCAGAGUUCCGAUUCAAAGGACAGAGCACAAAGUCAGACUCUGCAGAAGAUUAUCUAUUGUGGAAACGGCUGCAAGGUGUCUCUGCAGCUUGCCCUGCACCAAGCUCUGCAGCUCACCAACUAGAGCAUCUCAGUGCUAAGCUUCAGAAAAUUGACGAGCAGUUGCUAGCAAUACAGAACAUUGCUGAAAACAUAGAACAGGAUUUCCCCAAGCCUGAAAUGCUAGAUCUACAUUGUGAUAAGAUUGGACCAGUGGAUCACAUUGAAUUCUCUUCUGGCCCUGAAUUCAAAAAAACAUUAGCUUCAAAAACCAUUAGCAUUUCUGAAGAAGUGCGUUUUUUGACCCAUAUGGAUGAAGAAGAUCAAAGUGACAAAAAGGAGACUUCAGAACCUGAAUUUUCAAUAACAGAAAAUUAUUCUGGUCAGAAAACCUGUGUGUUUCCUACUGCCGAUUCAGCUGUCAGCCUUUCCAGUUCCAGUGAUCAGAAUACUACUUCUCCUGGUAUGAAUAGCAGUGAUGAAUUGUGUGAGAGUGUUUCAGUACAUCCGCUCCAGAUGACUGGAUUGACUGAUAUUGCAGACAUUAUUGAUGACCUUAUAAUUAAAGACGGAGUUUCCAGUGAAGAACUUGGCUUAACAGAACAAGCUAUGGGCACCUCCAGAAUUCAGCAUUAUUCUGGCAGACAUUCACAAAGAACUGACAAGGAAAGAAGAGAGAUUCAAGCCUGGAUGAAAAGAAAACGAAAAGAAAGAAUGGCAAAGUACUUAAAUGAGCUGGCAGAAAAGAGAGGGCAAGAACAUGAUCCUUUCUGUCCCAGAAGCAAUCCACUUUACAUGACUUCAAGGGAAAUAAGGCUGAGACAAAAGAUGAAGCAUGAAAAAGACAGAUUGCUGCUCUCUGAACACUAUAGUCGUCGAAUCUCACAAGCGUACGGUCUGAUGAAUGAACUGUUAUCUGAGUCAGUACAGCUACCAACUCUACCACAGAAACCAUUGCCUAACAAACCCAGCCCUACUCAGUCUUCCAGUUGUCAACACUGCCCUUCUCCAAGAGGAGAGAAUCAACAUGGUCACAGUUUUCUAAUAAAUCGACCUGGAAAAGUCAAAUAUAUGUCCAAACCGAGUUAUAUCCAUAAGAGGAAGUCUUUUGGGCAACCUCAAGGCUCACCUUGGCCACAUGGAACUGCCACUUUCACCAUACAGAAAAAAGCUGGUGGAGCCAAAGCAGCAGUAAGAAAGGCUACGCAGUCUCCAGUUACCUUCCAAAAAGGCUCUAAUGCUCCGUGUCAUAGUCUGCAGCAUACAAAAAAACAUGGAAGUGCUGGGCUUGCACCUCAAACCAAGCAGGUGUGUGUAGAGUAUGAAAGAGAGGAGACUGUGGUGAGUCCCUGGACGAUACCUUCAGAAAUCCAUAAGAUUCUUCAUGAGAGUCACAAUUCCCUUCUACAAGAAAACUUUGGACCUUAUUGAGAAGAGGAAAACACUUAAUUGGGCAGAAGUCCUAGUGGCACCCACCAGAGCUCUACUGCAUUCAGACACUGUUCACACACUGACCAUUCAUGUGUGUUCAGCAUCUGAACUUGGCCUUGUGACGUAGAGACCCUGAUGAAAGCUAAUGUUUCUGUUUUCAUGAAAAUAUUCAAUCUAGGGAACACCUUAGAGGAAAAAAGACUUUUAGGUAAGAUUGGUUUGGAAAUUGGGAAUGACCCAGCUUGUGCCUAUAUAUGUGGGCCUGCAAUCAACUUCUGUGGUAGGAGUGAGUUGCCUACCUGAAGGGAAACUUUUUACAUAGGAUUUAAAAAGAUGAUACUAAUUUAAAAACAAACAACAUUUUAAAUAGGUUCAAAGCUAGUGAAAGUAAAAAUAAACUAAUUAAUAUUACCCCAGUAUUAAGAAUUUAGCACACCUACAACCAUCUGAUCUUCAACAAACCUGACAAAAACAAGCAAUGGGGAAAGGACUCCCUAUUUAAUCAAUGGUGCUGGGAGAACUGGCUAGCCGUAUGCAGAAAAUUGAAACUGAACCCUUUCCUUACACCUUCAUACAAAAAUUAGUUCCAGAUGGAUUAAAGACUUAAAUGUAAAACCCAAAACUAUAAAAUCCCUAGAAGAAAAUCUAGGCAAUACUAUCUGGGACAUAGGCACAGGCAAAGAUUUUAUAAUGCAAAUACCAAAAUCACUUGCAACACAAGCAAAAAUUGACGACUGGGAUCUAAUUGAACUAAAGAGCUUCUGCACAGCAAAAGAAACUAUCACCAGAGCAAGUAGACAACUUACAGAAUGGGAGAACAUUUUUGCAAUCUGUCCAUCUGACAAAAGUCUAAUAUCCAGAGUCUACAAAUAACUUAAACAAAUUUACAAGAAAAAACCCCAUUAAAAAGUGGGCAAAGGACAUGAACAGACACUUCUCAAAAGAAGACAUGCAUAUGGCCAACAAACCUAUGAAAAGAAGCUCAACAUCACUGAUCAUUAGAGAAAUCCUAAUCAAAACCACAAUGAAAUACCAUCUCACACCAGUCAGAAUGGCAAUUAUUAAAAUGUCAAAAAAAAAAAAAAUAACAGAUGCUUCCGAGGUUGUGGAGGAAAAGGAACACCUUUACACUGUUGCUGGGAGUGUAAAUUAGUUUAACCAUUGUGGAAGACAGUGUGGCAAUUCCCCAAAGAUCUAAAAGCAGAAAUACCAUUUGACCCAGCAAUACCAUUGCUGGGUAUAUAUCCAAAGGAAUAUAAAUCAUUCUAUUAUAAAGAUACAUGGAUGCGUAUGUUCACUGCAGCACUAUUCACAAUAGCAAAUAUGUGGAAUCCAUCCAAAUGUCCAUCAUAGACUGGACAAAUAAAAUACUGUACACAUAUAUAUACACACCAUGAAAUACUAUGCAGCCAUAAAAAAGAACAAGAUCUUGUCAUUUGCAUGGAUAUGCAUGGAGCUGGAGGCCGUUAUCCUUAGCAAACUAAGGCAGGAACGGAAAACCAAACAGUGCAUAUUCUCACUUAUAAGUGGGAGCUGAAUGGUGAGAACACAUGGACACAUAGGGGGAACAACACGCCACUGGGGCCUGUUGAGGAGGGGAGGGAGAGAAUCAGGAAGAAUAGCUAAUGGAUGCUGGGCUUAACAUCUAGGUGAUGGGAUGAUCUGUACAGCAAACCACCACACCACACAUUUACCUAUGUAACAAACCUGCACAUCCUGCAUAUGUACCCCUUAAAAGCUGAAGAUAAAAAAUUGUUUUUUAGUGGUUUCUACCUGUAAUCUCACUUUGGGAGGCUGACGCAGGAGGAUCGCUUGAGCCCAGGAGUUUGAGACCAGCUUGGGCAACAAACAAAGGGAGAUCCCAUCUCUACAAAAAAUUAAAAAUUGCUGGGCACGGCGGUUUACACCUGUAAUCCCAGCACUUUGGGAGGCCAAGGUGGGAGGAUCGCUUGAGUCCAGGAGAUCAAGAUCAGUUUAGGCAAUAUAGUGAGACCCUGUCUCUACAAAAAAAAUUUAAAAAUUAGCCAGGUGUGUUGGUGUGUGCCUGUAGUCCCAGCUACUUGGGAGGCUGAGGUGGGAGGAUCACUUGAGCCUGAGAGGUCAAGGUUGCAGUGAGCCAUGAUCAUGCCACUUCACCCCAGCCUGGGUAACAGAGCGAGACCCUGUCUCAAAAAAAAAAAAAAAAAAAAAAAAAGACACACACACACACACAAGUUUCUUGAUAUAGUGUAUUCAUAAAUAUUUUUUAUUCUGUCUGUCUCUUAAGACCCAAGUGAAAGGAUAAUAAAUUUUAAAAAUAUAUAAAUCAAUGCAAACAAAGAGAAUUGGAAAAGAGACAAUUCUAGAUGAAAGAUUUCAACAAAUUUUCAGAAGACAGAAGACAAAAGCAGCAGCAACAGACGUAACAGGGUGGAGAAAGCCAUGAUAUAAUUUAUGCAAAAGAGGAUAGUGAUGAAAAGUGAACUUGAGACUCAGAGCUGAUAAGCACAAAAAGGGGCAUACCAGCUUUUUGAACAGGGGCAUGCAGCUGUUCUACAUAUGCACUAAUAAACCAUGAGACAACCAUGGUUUAUUAUUCCAUAUGUAGACUGGCUGCAACUCUUCAUCUCUGCAAACUUCUGCAAAGAAUUCCUAGCACCUAUACCCCAAGCAAGGGUCCAACUUCUCAUCUGAUUCGCCUUAGAGCAGAGGUCUGCAAAGUGGCUCAAUCCCUCUUCUUACAAAUAAGGUUUUAUUGAAAUGCAUCCUGUCUAUUCAUUUACAUAUUAUCUAUGGUAGAAUUGCAAAGUUGCAACAUAGACCUUACGGCCUGCAAAGCCUAAAAUAUUUUCUGGCCCUUUACAGAAAAAAGUUUGCUGGCUACUGCCCAGAGUAGAGCCUACCAGAGGAGCUUCACCUACACACUCAGCUUCUUCAGUAAAUGUUUUAGUAUCAUCUUUCCCUAAAACUAAAUAGACCACUAGGCAUCCUAGAUGCAUGGAGAAAAUCAUUAUGAAAGGGAAAAUCCAAAUUAAAUAGGCAAAAUAAUAGAGAAAAUAACUCAAGAAGAAAUAAAAGAAAUGGUUUUUAAAACUAAUUGGUAUGCUCAAUGACAAAGGGAACUCUAUUCUCACAUUUCUAUAAGGUUAUUAUUUCUUUGGAAAAAAGAGAAUUUAUGUUUCUGAUUGGUGAGUGGCAAGAGUUCAACAUCGCCAGGUGUGGUGGCUCAUGCCUGUAAUUCCAGCACUUUGGGAGAUUGAGGUGAGUGGAUCACUUGAGGUCAGGAGUUUGAGACCAGCCUGGCCAACAUGGUGAAACCCUGUCUCUACCAAAAAUACAAAAAUUAGCCAGGCGUAGUGGCAUGUGCCUGUAAUCCCAGCUAUUCGGGAGGCUAAGGCAUGAGAAUCACUUGAAUCUGGGAGGCGAAGGUUGCGGUGAGCAGAGAUUGCACCUGGGUAACAGAGUGAGACCUUGUCUCAAAAAAACAAAAACAAAAGAAAAAAAAAGUUUGACAUCAGUUGCUCCCCCCAGCCCAAAUUUUCUCUUUUCUUUUCUUUUUUUUUUUUUUGAGACAGGGUCUUGCUCUGUCACCUAGGCUAGAGUGCAGUGGUGUGAUCAUUGCCCACUGCAGCCUCUACCUCUUGUUCAAGUGAUCCUCCUGCCUUGGCCUCCUGAGUAGCUGGGACCACAGGUAAACACCACCAUGCCUGGCUAAUUUUUGUUUUUUGUUUUUUUUGUAGUGAUUGAUAGGGGUUUCACUAUGUUGCCUCAGCUGGUCUCUAACUCCUUGGCUCAAGCAAUCCUCCCAUCUCAGCCUCCCAAAGUGCUGGGAUUGCAGGUGUGAGCCACCGUGCCCAGCCUGUUUCCAUUUCUUAAGUGAGUGCAAUACCUGUAUUAAAAACCAAUUGCAUGUGACACUAUUCUUUCCCAACACUUGAGGCUUGACAAGUGAGGGGUAAGCAAUUUUUCUUUUGGUAGGCUGCCUAAAUAGAUAAGUAAGUAUCUGCCUUGCCAAAUACUCGACCCAGCAGAUGCAUUGCAAGGUCUAGAUUCCGGGAAGAAGGCAGCAAGCUUGAUUGUGAUUGCAGGUCCAGGUUACAAUGUGUUCUGUAUUCUGGCUCUACUGACAAUAAAGCUGUUAAUGUUACCUCCA